GUCACCCAGGCAGGUUCAGGGCUUUCUGGCUAUAAAAGGGAGCCUCUGGGAUCAGCAGGUCAUAUCUGGUGCCCAUGGUUGACUGAGGAGUCGGGUGAGGCCACCCUACCACAAGGGUCCCCCUCCCCAUCCUACACAGGAAUGAAAACAGUCCCAUGUACACUUUCUGGAAGCCUAAAUACCACCCACACCAUGUGGAAGGAAAGCAGGAGAGAGACUGAGUGGCACAUCCUUUCGCCCUCUUUUCUCUCGAACCUCCUCCCAGGCCGACCACCCUUGCUGUGUCCAAGCCAAGCUCUGUGGGCUUUCUGUUCCUCCUGAGUAGCUGAUUUUCAGAAUUUGGGGUACCAGGGCUCUGGGGAAUGUGAGCUAGAGAGCAGAUAAGUCUGGAAGAUGACCACUGACUCCUACUCUCCUACUUCUCCAGAUGCAGAGGCCUCCAUGGCUGUGAUAAGCCUGCUGUUCUUGGCAGUGAUGUAUGUUGUUCACCACCCUCUGAUGGUCAGUGAUCGGAUGGACCUGGACACAUUAGCCAGGAGUCGGCAGCUGGAGAAGCGAAUGAGUGAGGAGAUGCGCCUGCUAGAGAUGGAGUUUGAAGAGAGAAAGCGAGCCGCUGAGCAGAGGCAGAAGGCAGAGAACUUCUGGACAGGAGACACAUCCAGUGACCAGUUAGUGCUGGGGAAGAAAGACAUGGGGUGGCCGUUCCAGGCCGAUGGCCAGGAAGGGCCUCUGGGCUGGAUGCUGGGAAACCUGUGGAACACUGGCCUCUUUUGCCUUUUUCUCGUCUUUGAGCUCCUGCGACAGAACAUGCAGCAUGAACCGGCCUUUGAUUCCAGCAGUGAGGAGGAGGAGGAGGAAGUCCGUGUUGUCCCUGUCACCUCUUACAACUGGCUUACUGACUUCCCCUCCCAGGAGGCCCUGGACUCCUUUUACAAACACUAUGUCCAAAAUGCCAUCCGUGACCUGCCCUGCACCUGUGAGUUUGUGGAGAGUUUUGUGGAUGAUCUCAUUGAGGCCUGUCGGGUGCUCAGCCGCCAAGAGGCUCACCCACAAUUGGAAGACUGCCUGGGCAUCGGGGCUGCCUUUGAGAAAUGGGGAACCCUCCAUGAGACCCAGAAAUUUGAUAUCCUGGUGCCCAUUGUCCCCCCACAGGGCACCAUGUUUGUCCUGGAGAUGAGGGACCCAGCCCUGGGCCGCCGCUGUGGCUGUGUGCUGGUGGAGUCAGAAUGUGUGUGCAAGCGUGAGAAACUCCUAGGGGACGUGCUGUGCCUGGUGCACCACCACAGGGACCCCUCGGCAGUCUUGGGGAAGUGUAGUAGCUCCAUCAAGGCAGCUCUCUGCACCGGCUUCCACCUAGACGUGUGCAAGACUGUGCAGUGGUUCCGGAACAUGAUGGGCAAUGCCUGGGCCCUUGUGGCCCACAAGUAUGACUUUAAACUCAGUCUCCCACCGUCUACCACCUCCUGCAAGCUCCGGCUGGACUAUCGCUCAGGCCGCUUUCUCUCAAUCCACUUGGUCCUGGGGGUGCAACGAGAAGACACCUUGGUCUACCUGGUGAGUCAGGCUCCUGACCAGGAGCAGCUCACCAGUGUGGACUGGCCUGAGUCCUUUGUGGCCUGUGAGCACCUGUUCCUGAAGCUGGUGGGGCGCUUUGCCCCCGAGAACACCUGUCACCUCAAGUGCCUCCAGAUCAUUUUAAGUCUCCGGCAGCAUCAGAGCUUACCCCAUGGAGCAUCCCGCCCCAUCCUCACUUCUUACCAUUUUAAAACAGCUCUCAUGCACCUCUUGCUACGGCUGCCCCUCACGGACUGGGCCCACAACAUGCUCUCUCAGCGGCUCCAGGACAUUCUCUGGUUCUUGGGCCGUGGCCUCCAGCAAAGGUCCCUCCAUCAUUUCCUCAUUGGUAACAAUUUUCUGCCCCUGACCAUCCCAAUCCCUAAGACAUUUAGGAAUGCUGAGCCGGUCAAUCUCUUCCAACACCUGGUGCUCAACCCCAAGGCACAUUCACAGGCAGUGGAAGAGUUCCAAAACCUUCUGACCCAGGUGAAAACUCUGCCUCAUGCCCCACUGGCUGCAGCACCUUGAUGUAAAGACCAUUAAAAAAAAAACAGAGGAAGGUAUUUCUAAUUCCUUGGGCUACAAAAGUGUUUACUUUUCAGAUAUAUCAGUGGUAUAUGUGACCUUCACCUUGCCAGUGGGGGCUAUGAUGAGACACCUUAAGGAGCGUGUGAGGUGGUCAUGAGGAUGGGCAUAAUGACCCUGCAGGGCCUAGUCAAGGAUGGGUCAUCUGAGGUUUUCUUCUGCUAACUUUCAUCAUGACCCAAAGAAGGUCCAGGGAAACGGAUGUUAUGGGAGGAUCUUGCUGCUAAGGAGGUGAGAUCCAGAGGGUCACUGUGAAGUUGUGUUUUUGUAUCAACACUCGAAGUGAGAGAACCAGAGAAUACCUUCAUUCCAGCUUAUUCCUUUUUGUGAUUGACUUCCAGUAUGUUCCUUGUGAAUUGGUUUCCUUGUUGAACUGUUAGCUUAAUUCUCAUCCGAGCUGGUGGCACUCCAUUUUAUCCCAAAUACUGUGAUGGGCAACUUCUCAUAAUUUACGAUCUAAUUUUUCAAACCUUCACUAUUUUGAAAAUAUAACCAAGGCCGGUUGCGGUGGCUCACGCCUGUUAAUCCCAGCACUUUGGGGGGCCGAGGUGGGUGUAUCGCCUGAGUUCAGGAGUUCAAGACCACCCCGGGCAACAUGGUGAAACCCCAUCUCUGCUAAAAUACACAAAAUUAGCCGGGCAUGGUGGCGCGCACCUGUAGUCCCAGCUACUUGGGAGGCUGAGGCACGAGAAUCACUUAAGCCCCAGUGGUGGAGGUUGCAGUGAGCCGAGAUCGCACCACUACACUUCAGCUUGGACUACAGAGUGAGAAUCUGUCUCAAAAAAAAAAAAAUUAUAUAUAUAUAUAUAUAUAUAUAUAUAUAUAUAUAUAUAUAUAUCUCCAAGAUGUUUACAUUCCAUUUUCUUAACUUAGCCCUAUUUUCAUAUGACAAUAGAGUUGUUUUUAUGCAUCUGAAAAAACUACCUAAUUUAUUCGCAUUGAUUCACAAAUAUUAAGUCAAUAGUAACCUGUCUCAUAAUUGAGAUAAUGUAUUUACCAUAAUAAUGAAAUGGUUAACAUCUGAUGACCUUUUUAAGGUGCCUGGAGGCAACAUUAUAAAGGCCUUCACAAGGACAAUCUUUUUGGGGGCUCUGAGAUGAAUAAUUACUUUGUUGCUUGUGGGGAGCCACUUGUUGAGUGUAAAGAAGGUUUAGCUGCCAUGUUUAGCUGUGCUUUUUCUGUCUGGCCAUGCCUCCUUUGUAUUUUUUUUUUUUUUUUUCAAAAAUGACAAAGGGAUUACUUGAACUGUGUUUGUGGUUUUGAAAGAGAGGUCAUCACAAUCCAGGCUCACUGCCAGGUUUGUAUAGGAAAGGAUUGGGAAACAGUCCAACUCUAAAAUUGUGAUUCUAGAGAUAUAAUUGGUGUAUUUUUCCCUUUUUUCAAAACCAUGGGAUGCUGAGGAGGAGUGUUAAGAAAUGCAACUAUAGUUAUGGGUGUGAUUGUUUUGGAAACGCCAAUGCUGUUCUAUCUGCACUGCCAAGAAGAUCUGCUGGGGAGGGUAACCUGUCCCCACUGAACUUGACCUCAGCAGGGAUCAGAUGCUGGCCCUUAUAGGCUUCAGUCAUAGAAUACACACCCUCUCCUCCAGCAAAAAUAAAUUAAAAAUGUCCCAAAGCCAGGUGCAGUGGCUCACACCUGUAAUCCCAGCACUCUGGGAGGCUGAGGUGGGAAGAUCACUUGAGCCCAGGAGUUCAAGACCAGCCUGGGCAACAUGUCGCAAUCCCGUCUCUACAAAAAAUUAGCUGGGCAUGGUGGCAUAUACCUGUGAUCCCUGCUACUCUGGAGGUUGAGGCGGAAAGACUGCUUGAGCCCAGGAGGUCAGGGCUGUAGUGAGCUAUGAUAGUGUCACUGUGCUCCAGCGACCCUGGGCAAAAAAGUGAGACCGCGUCUCAAAAAAAAAAAAAAAAAAAAAAAAAAAAAAGGUUCCCAGAAGCUGAUGCCAGUCAAUCAUUGGGGCUCCCAGUGCACAAUAGCUACUGUGUUCCUGUGUUGCCUGCAUCUGUCAGGUACCGCUUUCAAUGCAAGAUGCAAUCAUGGUUGCUUCCCUGCUGAUGGGAUUUUGGUGUUUUAGCAACAUUCACAUACUUUUUGUUUAGAAAAUUAUUUGCUGAUGUUUUAAGUUAAAGUCAAUAAAGGAGGCUAUUUUCUGUA